GGAGGUGUCAUCUGUGGACAAUACCUGGAAGGGCAAGGGGUGGUGGGUGUCACUAAAAGGAACCAGCCCCAGCUACUUCACUGCAGGCUGGUGCCCUGGUGAAGGUGAAUCAGUCAGAGGAGUGCUGACUGCCCAUGGGGCUGCACCAUAUCAUGGUUCCCACUAGCAAUAUAUGAGAGUUCCAGUUGCUCCACAACCUCGCCAACAUAUGACAGGUGCUGCAAGAGGAUGGUUAUUUAACGCUGGCCCCCAAGGAGGAAGGCACAGACCUUCCUCCUCCUGGAACAUCCAAGGGCACUGGAUCCUCUGUGUCCCUCUGAGAUGGGGUGCCACUCCAGCAAGAGCACCACGGUGGCAGCUGAGUCCCAGAAGCUUGAAGAAGAGCGCGAGGGAAGAGAGCCAGGUCUGGAGACCGGCACCCAGGCAGCAGACUGCAAGGAUGCCCCGCUGAAGGAUGGAACCCCUGAGCCAAAGAGCUGAAAUGCCUCUCUCCAGAGUCGGACCCUCACCUCCUUCCUGGAACUGCCUUUGGCCCCAGAACCAUGAGACAAUCCCCACCCUGAGAAGCUCCGAUCACUGGGAGGAGAGAGAAAGCCUCCAGCUUUGGGAUUCAGGCUUCAGAAGUUUUUAGCAGCCUUUGCUCAUUGGAGAGGUGGGGAGGAUAAGUCUAUAAGGAAUCCUAUUUCCCCAGCUCUCCCACAGAGAGGACAAAAGAAGUCUUCACACGUUGUGGAACUUUCCUGCAACUUCUGGAUGCAGACAAGCCUCAGAGCAGACUGUUCUGGCUCCAGUGAAUAUCGGCUGCCAAGCUGUGAGCAUCCAGGGAUCCCCGUCUGCCUGGCUUUCCUGAAGUCAGAAGGCGCCUUGGUCAUACUGUGUGGGGUGUGUGGAUCUCAGUUUGCUCUCUUUCUUUCUCCUUUUUUCAACAGCUGGCGGAGUAGCCAACACCCCUGACAGCAAUGUGUUGCACUUGGCUCACUCCACACCCUAUGAAUAAUUUUAAUAUUUAACUUGAAAUGUUGUUAAGAAACUAUGGAAAAUAUCAGGAUCCCACUGGGAUCCCGUAAAUUGAAGGCAACAAGGUCUUGGUCCUCCAGUAAGGGGGGCAUGGAGCCCUGGUGGGAAGGAAAGAAGAGAAAUUUGUGUUCCUGAUUCCUUAAUCCCCAAGAAAGGUCCCUCUGCUAACAUUCACAUAUCUCUUCCUAGCCAAAGUCUGUCCAUUUCAACCCUCUAGCAUCUGAGCUAUCUGCAUCCAGCUUUCAAAAAUAUUUCGCUGUUUACUAACAUGUCUGUCAGCCUCUCUUUUCUCCCCCGCAUGUGUUUUGUUUUUAAAUCCACUCAAAAGCGUUUUCAUUUGAAAUCAAAUAGACAUGUUUGCAAAUAAAUGUUGACACAACACAUUUGAAAGACAGAAUUGGGGAUCUGAGAUUAAGAGUAUCAGCAGAGAAGAGUGGGUGUAAUUCUGUGGAACAGGAGUGAGAACAGAGGCGAGGGAGCCGUUGCUUUGUGCCAGGCGCCAUGCUGAGGACUUUCCAUAGACGGUUUAAUGCCACCCAACUACUCCCAUUUUAUAGAUGAGGAAAUGGAGGAAAUAAAGUCACUUGCCUGAGUUUGGGCAGCCAGGAAGGAGCAGAACCCACAGUUGAGCCCCAGCAGUUUGGCUUGGGAAACGCAUGUAGAGUGCUUCUUAAAGCAGAGAGCCUUUCUCAUGAUUAAACUGAAAUACUAGUCCCUUUAUAGCCUGUGCAUAGUGAGGACCAUUUUUCUUUAUUCACUGAGACCUACCUGCCUAUUGAGAAGUAUGUAACCGGUCAGCUUGGAGUUGCCCCACUGCAGGUUGGGUGAUGCAUUGAGGGACUUUUUAUUUUUACUCUGGUGGUGGGGGACGGGGAGGGAGGAAGAGACGGAGAGGGAAGUGGGAGAAGGGAGGGAGGGAAGGGAGGAAAGAUGAAGAAAGGGAGGAGGGAGAGGAGGGGGGAAGGGAGAGAAAGAGGAAAGAGGUAGGGAGAGGGAGAAGAGGAGGGAGGAGAGAGGGCAAGAAGAAAAAGGAGGAGGGGAAACAGAGGAAGAGAGGGAGGAGGGAAAGAAGGAGAGGGAGAGAAAGGGAAGAGGUAGGGAGAUGAAAGAGCGGGGAGAGGCAGAAUGGGAGAGGGAGAGAAGGAGAGGGGAGACGGAGGGAGGAAGGGAGAGAAAGGAGAGGGGUGAGGGAAAAGGGGUAGGGAGGAGGGAGGAAGAGAAAAAUGGGGAGAGGGUGGGCGAGAAGGAAAGGAAGAAAUCGAGGAAGUUGGAGGAAUGAGGGAUGAGGCAGGGAGGGAGAAAGGGAGGGCGAAGCAGUAAGGUGCUGCAAAGGACCCUUCUUUUUGGCCAUAAAAACCUGAGAAACUGAUUGAGAUUCUUUUGAGCAAUAAGGCAACUGCGGUGAGGAAAAAAUAAGGAAGGAGGCACAAAAAGCAAAGCAGUUCAGCCUGAAAUUGACUACAGAGCUUCCCUUUGCUUCAGCAGAGCCUGGAGGAGCAGGAGGGAUGGGGGCCCUGUCAGCUGGCCCAAAGCCCUGCCCUGUCCCAGGGGUGCUAAGCUUGCUGCAGGCCAGGAAACAGGCCUGGGCUUGCAGCUGGGGAUCAGGAAGUUUGGGGCCUCUUUGCACAGCUUACUGGGGAUAGGCCAAGCUCUGGGAACUCCUUUCAAUUUUUUUUUUUUUUAAGACAACUCUGUUUUUCUCCCUCCUCCCUACUAGUGGAAAUUUACCUUGCAAAACAGGACUGUGCAUGGUGAGAGCUGCUUGCAAUGUCCACACUCAGGACUCUAUGGAAAGAGUUCGCAGCUGGUGGUGAGGCUUUGAGGUGGGGCUGCCCUUAUUUCACUAGCUCCUGAGGGGCAGAGCUCACUCAGCUUUUUACCAAAUCAAAGGAAGGAAGCUUUAGGUCCUUCGAAGUUCAGAACCAGGGUGGUUUGUUUUGCUUCCUUUUGGAAUGGAAUAAAAUGCUCAUUUAAUUAAA